GCGUUCCAUUGGUGCCCUGGUUACGCCACCUGUGGCUCAGUUGCACAGCUGCCUGGUAGGUGACUGGAGGCAUUGAGCAGUGCUCACUGGUAUUUCGCUGAUGUGGCCCCAACCCCGCCUCCCUCCCCACCCCGCGAUGUCAGAAAAAACACAACAGGGGAAAUUGGCCGCAGCCAAGAAAAAGUUAAAAGCAUAUUGGCAGAGGAAGAGCCCUGGCAUUCCAGCAGGAGCUAACAGGAAAAAGAAAGUCAAUGGCAGUAGCCCUGACACAGCCACUUCUGGUGGUUACCACUCACCUGGGGAUUCAGCAACAGGUAUCUACGGGGAGGGCCGUGCAUCCUCUACUACCCUGCAGGAUCUGGAGAGCCAGUACCAAGAACUAGCAGUGGCCCUGGAUUCAAGCUCCGCAAUAAUCAGUCAACUCACUGAAAACAUCAAUUCACUGGUUCGCACAUCUAAGGAGGAGAAGAAGCAUGAGAUACAUCUGGUACAGAAGCUUGGGAGGAGCUUGUUCAAACUCAAAAACCAGACGGCUGAACCCCUGGCCCCAGAGCCCCCAGCAGGGCCAUCUAAGGUGGAGCAGCUACAAGAUGAGACCAACCACCUAAGGAAGGAGCUAGAGAGUGUGGGAAGACAGCUCCAGGCUGAGGUGGAAAACAAUCAGAUGUUGAGUCUCCUGAACAGGAGACAGGAGGAGAGGCUACGUGAACAGGAGGAGAGGCUACAUGAACAGGAGGAGAGGCUACAUGAACAGGAGGAGAGGCUGUGUGAACAGGAGGAGAGGCUACGUGAACAGGAGGAGAGGCUGUGUGAACAGGAGGAGAGGCUACGUGAACAGGAGGAGAGGCUACGUGAACAGGAGGAGAGGCUACGUGAACAGGAGGAGAGGCUACAUGAACAGGAGGAGAGGCUACAUGAACAGGAGGAGAGGCUGUGUGAACAGGAGGAGAGGCUACGUGAACAGGAGGAGAGGCUGUGUGAACAGGAGGAGAGGCUACGUGAACAGGAGGAGAGGCUGUGUGAACAGGAGGAGAGGCUACGUGAACAGGAGGAGAGGCUGUGUGAACAGGAGGAGAGGCUAUGUGAACAGGAGGAGAGGCUGUGUGAACAGGAGAAGCUGCCAGGGCAGGAGAGGCUGCUGGAAGAGGUGGAGAAGCUGUUAGAACAGGAGAGGCGGCAGGAGGAGCAGGAGAGGCUGCUGGAGAGGGAGAGGCUGCUGGACGAGGUGGAGGAGCUCCUGGAGCAGGAGAGGCUUCGGCAACAGGAUGAGAGGCUGUGGCAGCAGGAGACUCUGCGGGAGCUGGAGAGGCUGCGGGAGCUGGAGAGGCUGCGGGAGCUGGAGAGGAUGCUGGAGCUGGGGUGGGAAGCCCUGUACGAGCAGCGGGCCGAGCCACGCAGCGGCUUCGAGGAGCUGAACAACGAGAACAAGAGCACACUGCAGUUGGAGCAGCAAGUAAAGGAGCUGGAGAAGUCGGGUGGAGCUGAAGAGCCAAGAGGCUCCGAGUCUGCAGCAGCAGCCAGACCAGUACCUGGAGCCCCAGUCCCACAAGGAGCUUGGAUGUGCGGACAAGCAGGGUGGACUCCCCAGGAGCACCCAGGCUUGAGUGGAGAAGCUGUUGGUACAGGAGAGGCGGCAGGAGGAGCAGAAGAGGCUGCAUGCCAUUCUUUUCGGGCUGCGGAGAACAGGGAGCUAAACAUCACCAUCAUCUAAGAGCGGGUCAAGAAAUUGAAAAAAAAAAAAAA